GGAAGUAGGAGCUCUCAGAGGCUAAGAAGGUGGAGACCGGAGAAGCUGUGAGGUUCUUUAGCGUCACCUCCCUCACUGGGCAGCAUGGGGGAGAAGUCAGAGAACUGUGGGGUUCCAGAGGAUCUGUUAAAUGGUUUGAAGGUUACAGAUACUCAGGAAGCCGAGUGUGCUGGCCCUCCAGUUCCUGAUCCCAAAAAUCAGCAUUCCCAGAGUAAGCUGCUCAGGGAUGAUGAGGCCCAUCUCCAGGAGGACCAGGGAGAAGAGGAGUGUUUUCAUGACUGCAGUGCCUCAUUUGAGGAGGAGCCAGGAGCGGACAAGGUUGAGAACAAAUCUAAUGAAGAUGUGAAUUCCUCUGAACUAGAUGAAGAAUACCUAAUAGAACUGGAAAAAAACAUGUCGGAUGAAGAGAAACAGAAAAGAAGAGAAGAGAGCACUAGACUAAAGGAGGAGGGAAAUGAACAGUUUAAGAAAGGAGAUUAUAUAGAAGCUGAAAGUUCUUAUAGUCGAGCCCUCGAAAUGUGCCCAUCCUGCUUCCAAAAGGAGAGGUCGAUUCUAUUUUCAAAUAGAGCUGCAGCAAGGAUGAAACAGGACAAGAAAGAAAUGGCCAUCAAUGACUGCAGCAAAGCAAUUCAAUUAAACCCCAGCUAUAUCAGGGCAAUAUUGAGGAGAGCAGAGUUGUAUGAGAAGACGGACAAGCUAGAUGAAGCCCUGGAAGACUAUAAAUCUAUAUUAGAAAAAGAUCCAUCAAUACAUCAAGCAAGAGAAGCUUGUAUGAGAUUACCUAAGCAAAUUGAAGAACGUAAUGAAAGACUAAAAGAAGAGAUGUUAGGUAAAUUAAAAGAUCUUGGGAACUUGGUUCUCCGACCUUUUGGGCUCUCCACGGAAAAUUUCCAGAUCAAACAGGAUUCCUCUACCGGCUCGUACUCCAUCAAUUUCGUUCAAAAUCCAAAUAAUAACAGAUAACAAAGAUAACAAAAGCUUUACAAGCUGACUUGGAAUUGUGUGCUGCUUGCUGUUAGCUAGGGGAAAGGCCCUGCCAAUGUUUAACUUUUAAAAGCAUCUUAUCUAAAAGAAAGGCUAUCCAGUAGAGCCCAGUGCUCCCUUGUCCCUCUUUUAUGAUCAGGGUGAAAUGUACUUCCUGAUGUAAUGAACCUAAUUUGAUUUCCAUUUUAAGGUGGUGUCUGUGCAGCUGGUGUCCCCGAUUCUGGCUGUCCUAUGUCCAGGAAGAAGCCCAUUUGUUGAGGCUGACCUUCCUGAUCAUACACACACACAGCCCAGCAAAAGCCUCUCCUGAACCAAACAAACCUGUUGGUUGGGAGACUGCCCAGACAUGAUUGAUGACGGGUUCCCGCCUGCUGUCCCCUCCCUGAUCACACAGCUAACGAGGCUGCCUCCAGCAUUUCCUGAUUUCCUCUGUGGUAAUAAAAGCUUUCUGUGCUUA